AGUCCCGGGCCCGGAGCCAGCGCAUGCGCCCGCCUGUGGGCGCUGUCCCGGCUGCGAGGGCCGUGAGCUCACGGACCGACGGACCGACGGGCGGCCGGCCGGACAGACGGGGCAGCGCAGGGAGCGGGGACGCGGCGGGACAGCGACAUGGCCGGCCACACGCAGCAGCCGAGCGGGCGCGGGAACCCCAGGCCUGCGCCCUCGCCCUCCCCAGUCCCAGGGACCGUCCCCGGCGCCUCGGAGCGGGUGGCGCUCAAGAAGGAGAUCGGGCUGCUGAGCGCCUGCACCAUCAUCAUCGGGAACAUCAUCGGCUCGGGCAUCUUCAUCUCGCCCAAGGGGGUCCUGGAGCACUCAGGCUCCGUGGGUCUGGCCCUGUUCGUCUGGGUCCUGGGUGGGGGCGUGACGGCUCUGGGCUCCCUCUGCUAUGCAGAGCUGGGAGUCGCCAUCCCCAAGUCUGGCGGGGACUACGCCUACGUCACAGAGAUCUUCGGGGGCCUGGCUGGCUUUCUGCUGCUCUGGAGCGCCGUCCUCAUCAUGUACCCCACCAGCCUUGCUGUCAUCUCCAUGACCUUCUCCAACUACGUGCUGCAGCCCGUGUUCCCCAACUGCAUCCCCCCCACCACAGCCUCCCGGGUGCUGUCCAUGGCCUGCCUGAUGCUCCUGACAUGGGUGAACAGCUCCAGUGUGCGCUGGGCCACGCGCAUCCAGGACAUGUUCACAGGCGGGAAGCUGCUGGCCUUGUCCCUCAUCAUCGGCGUGGGCCUUCUCCAGAUCUUCCAAGGACACUUCGAGGAGCUGAGGCCCAGCAAUGCCUUUGCUUUCUGGAUGACGCCCUCCGUGGGACACCUGGCCCUGGCCUUCCUCCAGGGCUCCUUCGCCUUCAGUGGCUGGAACUUCCUCAACUAUGUCACCGAGGAGAUGGUUGACGCCCGAAAGAACCUACCUCGCGCCAUCUUCAUCUCCAUCCCACUGGUGACCUUCGUGUACACGUUCACCAACAUUGCCUACUUCACGGCCAUGUCCCCCCAGGAGCUGCUCUCCUCCAAUGCGGUGGCUGUGGUGAGUGGGCCCCUGCUCGGUCCCUGGCUCCUGCCCAGGCCCCUGCCCCGGCCUUACACAUGGCCUCUCUACUGUGCCCACCCAGACCUUCGGGGAGAAGCUGCUGGGCUACUUUUCUUGGGUCAUGCCUGUCUCCGUGGCUCUGUCAACCUUCGGAGGGAUCAAUGGUUACCUGUUCACCUACUCCAGGUGACUGCACUGGGGAGACGUGGGCAUGGGGAGGGAAGGCUGGGGUGCAGGUGUGCACCAGUCAUGCCGUGGGCCAGAGGAAGGGACACCUGCCGGGGGAGGGGUCUGCCUGAAGCUGGGAUGAUGAUCCCACACGGUAACAAGUGUCUGAUCACAACUGGGAGGCAAAGAAAGCAAGAGGCAGGCAGGCUGGAUGAGGGGGAGAACUGUCCAGUGGGGCUGCUGGGCCCGGAGCAGGAGGUCAGAGGCGACAGCUUAAGAGGGACAUCAGGUCCAAAGCUGAGACCCAGGAUGUGGCCAGUGCCCAUAUCUGUCCCCAACGCUAGGCUGUGCUUCUCUGGAGCCCGCGAGGGGCACCUGCCCAGCCUGCUGGCCAUGAUCCACGUCAGACACUGCACCCCCAUCCCCGCCCUCCUCGUCUGUUGCGGGGCCACAGCCGUCAUCAUGCUCGUGGGCGACACGUACACGCUCAUCAACUAUGUGUCCUUCAUCAACUACCUCUGCUACGGCGUCACCAUCCUGGGCCUGCUGCUGCUGCGCUGGAGGCGGCCUGCACUCCACAGGCCCAUCAAGGUGAACCUUCUCAUCCCCGUGGCGUACUUGGUCUUCUGGGCCUUCCUGCUGGUCUUCAGCUUCAUCUCAGAGCCUAUGGUCUGUGGGGUCGGCGUCAUCAUCAUCCUUACGGGGGUGCCCAUUUUCUUUCUGGGAGUGUUCUGGAGAAGCAAACCAAAGUGUGUGCACAGACUCACAGAGUCCAUGACACACUGGGGCCAGGAGCUGUGUUUCGUGGUCUACCCCCAGGACGCCCCCGAAGAGGAGGAGAAUGGCCCCUGCCCACCCUCCCUGCUGCCUGCCACAGACAAGCCCUCGAAGCCACAAUGAGAUUUUUGUAGAGACUGAAGCAGUUGUUUCUGUUUACAUGUUGUUUAUUGAGGAGGUGUUUUGGCAAAAAAGUUUUGUUUUGUUUUUUUCUGGAAAAAAAAGAAAAAAGAUACGACUCUCAGAAGCCUGUUUAAGGAAGCCCUAAAAUGUGGACUGGGUUUCCUGUCUUAGCACUGCCCUGCUAGCUCUUCCUGAAAAGGCCUAUAAAUAAACAGGGCUGGCUGUUC